CUCUCCGCGCGUCCCCUCUGCGCGCGGCGAGGCCGAGACGUCUCCCGCGGUGACAGCGUGCAAGGCGGAGACCCGGCGCGCUCCCAGCCCAGGGAAAGCCCAGGCGACGCGACCGCAAGCCCGAGCCCAGGUCCCUCGGAGCCGCCAGGGCGCGCCGGGCUGCUUGCCUUCCUGCCCCUUCCUGCAGGAAUCCCCCGCCGCCCGCGGCCGGGACUCCGGGCCUCUCCCGGGCGUAGAUUCCAGUCACCGCUCUGGGUCGGGGUUUCCCUCUUUCUGAAAUCCGUGCGGAAGGACCCCUCCCGGGGCCCCUCGCCCUGGCCCCAGACACCCUCCCUCCCAGACCCCGCGCUCCAGAUGCGCUGCCCCGCAGCUCCCUGACAGCUGCGAGCCCACGAACCCCGGCGGGAGGGCGGCGGCGGCGGACUGACAUGCCCCGGACGCGGCUGCGGCCGGCGGGCAGCCCGCGGGGGCGAUGAGCCGCUGCGACCGGUGAGGCGCCGGGCGGCGGGGGCAUCGCGUACCUUCCUCACCCCCCUCCCUUGCCCACUCCGCUCGGGAGGCCGAGAGGAAACGGUCUCUGGCCUAUCAGGAGGACAACUGGUGCUGCAAUAGAAGCCAGUGGCUAAGUCUCGUGUAUGGCGUGGUUAAGGUUGCAGCCUCUCACCUCUGCCUUCCUCCAUUUUGGGCUGGUUACCUUUGUGCUCUUCCUGAAUGGUCUUCGAGCAGAGGCUGGUGGCUCAGGGGACGUGCCAAGCACAGGGCAGAACAAUGAGUCCUGUUCAGGGUCAUCGGACUGCAAGGAGGGUGUCAUCCUGCCAAUCUGGUACCCGGAGAACCCUUCCCUUGGGGACAAGAUUGCCAGGGUCAUUGUCUAUUUUGUGGCCCUGAUAUACAUGUUCCUUGGGGUGUCCAUCAUUGCUGACCGCUUCAUGGCAUCUAUUGAAGUCAUCACCUCUCAAGAGAGGGAGGUGACAAUUAAGAAACCCAAUGGAGAAACCAGCACAACCACUAUUCGGGUCUGGAAUGAAACUGUCUCCAACCUGACCCUUAUGGCCCUGGGUUCCUCUGCUCCUGAGAUACUCCUCUCUUUAAUUGAGGUGUGUGGUCAUGGGUUCAUUGCUGGUGAUCUGGGACCUUCUACCAUUGUAGGGAGUGCAGCCUUCAACAUGUUCAUCAUCAUUGGCAUCUGUGUCUACGUGAUCCCAGACGGAGAGACUCGCAAGAUCAAGCAUCUACGAGUCUUCUUCAUCACCGCUGCUUGGAGUAUCUUUGCCUACAUCUGGCUCUAUAUGAUUCUGGCAGUCUUCUCCCCUGGUGUGGUCCAGGUUUGGGAAGGCCUCCUCACUCUCUUCUUCUUUCCAGUGUGUGUCCUUCUGGCCUGGGUGGCAGAUAAACGACUGCUCUUCUACAAAUACAUGCACAAAAAGUACCGCACAGACAAACACCGAGGAAUUAUCAUAGAGACAGAGGGUGACCACCCUAAGGGCAUUGAGAUGGAUGGGAAAAUGAUGAAUUCCCAUUUUCUAGAUGGGAACCUGGUGCCCCUGGAAGGGAAGGAAGUGGAUGAGUCCCGCAGAGAGAUGAUCCGGAUUCUCAAGGAUCUGAAGCAAAAACACCCAGAGAAGGACUUAGAUCAGCUGGUGGAGAUGGCCAAUUACUAUGCUCUUUCCCACCAACAGAAGAGCCGUGCCUUCUACCGUAUCCAAGCCACUCGUAUGAUGACUGGUGCAGGCAAUAUCCUGAAGAAACAUGCAGCAGAACAAGCCAAGAAGGCCUCCAGCAUGAGCGAGGUGCACACCGAUGAGCCUGAGGACUUUAUUUCCAAGGUCUUCUUUGACCCAUGUUCUUACCAGUGCCUGGAGAACUGUGGGGCUGUACUCCUGACAGUGGUGAGGAAAGGGGGAGACAUGUCAAAGACCAUGUAUGUGGACUACAAAACAGAGGAUGGUUCUGCCAAUGCAGGGGCUGACUAUGAGUUCACAGAGGGCACGGUGGUUCUGAAGCCAGGAGAGACCCAGAAGGAGUUCUCCGUGGGCAUAAUUGAUGACGACAUUUUUGAGGAGGAUGAACACUUCUUUGUAAGGUUGAGCAAUGUCCGCAUAGAGGAGGAGCAGCCAGAGGAGGGGAUGCCUCCAGCAAUAUUCAACAGUCUUCCCUUGCCUCGGGCUGUCCUAGCCUCCCCUUGUGUGGCCACAGUUACCAUCUUGGAUGAUGACCAUGCAGGCAUCUUCACUUUUGAAUGUGAUACUAUUCAUGUCAGUGAGAGUAUUGGUGUUAUGGAGGUCAAGGUUCUGCGGACAUCAGGUGCCCGGGGUACAGUCAUCGUCCCCUUUAGGACAGUAGAAGGGACAGCCAAGGGUGGCGGUGAGGACUUUGAAGACACAUAUGGGGAGUUGGAAUUCAAGAAUGAUGAAACUGUGUAUGCAGGAUCAGCAGACACCACUGGACAGGUUCUGCUUCCAAACUCUUCUUCAGUUUUCUCACUUUAAAUUGUUUCUGGGCAAGGAAUCCUGUGACAAGAGCUAAGGACACAAAACAUUUUCUUCUCUGAAACACAAAAUGAUAGCUGGUGGAGCUGUGGGAUGACAGAAGUUUUGUGAUAUCAGAUUUUGGAGAAUUCUUGUGACUAAGAAGGACUAGAGAACUGCUUGGGCCUCUUCUUCCUCCCUUCCUCAUAUGAAGGGUAUCUAUGAGCUUUGAAACCAAUCCUUUCCAUUCUGGGCAGCAAUAGCCCAUCAGAACAUUCUAAAGAAAACAAGUGGCAUUGGCUUUGUUCCCUGGUACUAUAUUGCCAGUCUCACUGUGUAACCAGAUUCCAGGCACGUCUUCUUUAAUUUGGAAAUUGCAAAAUUGAUAGAAAUUUAGCAAUCUUUUUAAAUGACCAUAGACUAUUUAAUGGUGUGAGGCUUGCCCAGCCUAGUUGAAUUGAGUCAGUAUGGUUUGGAUACUGGAAAGUAUCUUGGAGAAGCAGAGCUCCCAGGGCAGUGGCUACUUGUCUUUAGUCACAGGUCUAAGCUCCAAAAUCUGGUGAAGCAGUGAAGGAGAAACAUCCUAGGAAUUGUGGGAGGAAAUAUAUCUUCUGUGUGGUCCUCUCUUUUCACAGUCUAGGACUCUCCUGAAGUACCUCUUCUUGGGCUACUGCCCCAUUCAGCCCUUCAGAAACUGUGGGUAUUACACUUCUGUCACCUCUAUUACCCUAAGGCCUCUGCCCAUUGAACCCUCUUGCAAAUUGGUUAUUCUGUCCUUUUUCCAGUUGGAUAGCUUUAAAAGGGAAAGCAGAAUGACUUUCCUCAGGAUUUGUAGCUUAUGAGAAAGUAGACUUUCUUGGGUGGCCUAGAAGGUUGGAGAAGACAAACGGGAACUUCCUCUGAAUGACUGAACAUAUCCACAAAUAAUAAGCGUGGCAGGAGAUGGUGUGAAGAGUAAAAGGAGCAUAUAGGAAGUUGUGUGUGUGGGGUGUCUGUUUCAAGAACCUGCUAAUUAUACCUUCAGUAAGAAAUGAAGCCAUACAACCUCUAGAAGAGGAGGAGGAAGGAACUCAUGGAAAAGUGGGGAGCCAUAGAAGCUAGGGAGAGGUGUCCUAGGAGUGCUUCUGCCCAGGUCCAGCCAUGAGACAGAGCUCAAAAAGAGCUGGGCACUGCUGGUGACAGAACUGAGUGACCCGGGGGAUCCUGCAUCUGUUCUUACUCAAUCCCUUCUUAAUAAUGUGACUUGGGGCAGGUCAUUUAUUGGUUCUGGAACUUAACUUUCUGAUAUGCAAACUGGGAAUAACAAUACUUUCCUUGCCUGGAGGCAAGGUCAGUCCUUUUUGCAGUUCCUUCCAGCUCUAAGAUUUUCUGAACCAUAGACAUAAGCACUCAGUGUAGGUCAUAUUCGCACUUGCCAAAAAUGGAUCAGGGGAUAUUGUCUCCUGAAGGGAAAUGGCCAUUGACAAAUUGAUUUAUUAGAGCUCUGUUUAGUCAUUUUGCUGGGAAGGAUAAUCAUUUGUUAACGUAAGUAGAAACCUGUGCCUUCUGGAGAAUACUAUCCAUUUAUAUGUACUCUGGGGAGAGUGUUUAUACAUACAAAUGAAGGACAGGGCUUCACUGGGAAAACAAACUCCAUGGAAUUUCACAUGAUUAUCGCGAUGUCAGUGUGGAAGAAGAUAUGGUAAGGCAUUAAAUGACAUUAAGACCACAAAAUUUGCCAUAAUUUGACGGACUUGUGGUUCUUCUGAUUCAGAACCCUUUCUACCCAUGUCACGGAUAGGUAGUUUUUCAGAGAUCAGAGGCUUAGUUCAUUCUAUUAAUUUCCUCAUUCUAUUAAUAAUCAAUUAUGCACCUAGGGUCUCUGAAUACGACUAAACCUUCCUCAAACUUAUUUGCGUUUUCAGUUUGUAUAAUAUCUUGGUGCAAAUGAGCCUCGCAAAUGAUCACUUCUGGGUAAUACUCAUUCUAAAGGUAUGUCAACCUUGAGAAUUCUGGUCUAGAUAUUCUAGGGUUUGGUGAACAAAUCUAUGUUCCCAUCCAUCCCUUUUCAUUUAUUUUUUAGACUUCAUUCAUUGCAGAAUAAUGAGUCCAAAACCUGCUCAUCUGUUCUCACGUGGCACCCCUAUUCUUGAUAUUUUAAAUUGCAAUUUUACAACUAGAGGCAGUAUUACGGAGCAGAAAAAUCGUGGGUUCUAAGUACUCUGGGUUAGGAUUCUGGCUCCACUACUGAUUUAAUAAUGUAGUUUGGGGAAAUUUUAUUAACCUAUGAAAUUAUUUCCUCAUUGGCAAAAUGGGGAUAAUAAUAUCUCUCUUGCAGGGCCAUUAUGACGAUUCAAGGUAUUGUAUGCGGUGUACCUGGUACACGGUAUAUGCUCAGGAAACAAGACUCUUCAUAGUAAUAUUGACGAAUUAACAAUAUUCUUCAGAAGACACUGUGGAGUUGUUUAGGUUACUUGGCUCUUUGUGUGACCCUAAGUAAUGAGCAUGCCAGUUUGGGGUUACUAUGAAGAGUACUUACCUAAACUCAUAAAAUAUUAGAGCUAGAAAGGACCUUAGAAUAUCUUCUGCAGUCAUGGUUCUUAAAUUUUAAUGUGUUGCUCAAUCAUCCAGGGAUCUCACUGAAGGGCAGAUUAGGAUCCAGGAGGUCUAGGGGAGGGAUUGAGAUUCCGCAUUUCUAACAAGUUCUGGAUGCUGCGGGCCCCAACUUAGAGGUGAAAGGUUCUGAAGCUCUUGACCAAACCAGGAGACCCAGCAAAGAAGUGGUUUUUCAGACAACUUGCUUAAUUGAAUAAUGAUUGUUUGCUCUUUAAUUCCAACUUUCAACGCCAAUUUAGCAAGAACCAGAGGCUGUGCUAAUUGCCACACCAGUCUGGAAACCGAAAUGGAUAGCUUCAGGGUACUUGGACAAAGUUGGAACAUCUGCUUUCUAAUCUCUCCCUCUUUGUAUAGCUUUAUUUGCCUACCAAGCCUGGUAGUAUUGAAAAUCUGCCCUCACUAUACUCCCCUAAAUAUAAUCAAGUUGAGGCCAGGCCUGUGCUCUAUCAAUAAUAUAGGAUCCACGAAUUCACAUGUUUGGUUUUAUGCUUUACUUCUUCAAAGGUGCUUUUAGCAGCAUGGAAGAAUGGAAAAGCACGAGCUUUGGAAUAUGAAAGCAGAUGUGAAUCCAUCACUUACCAGUAACUUUUAACAAGUCACAUCACUUUUCUGAGUACCAGGUUUUUGUUGGACAACAGAAAUAAUAUUCUCUAUCCUUCAAGGGAAUACUAAAUAUAAGUAUGAGAAAAAUGCACAGUGCCUUCUCGUAGAUGGUGUUCAGUCAUUCAACAAACAUUUGUUAGAUAUUUGCUAUGUACUAGCUACAUUACUAGGCACUGGGGUUAAAUAAGUGAAUAAGACAAGCUGACAUUUCAGCGCUCAAGGAUCUUACUGUCAAGUGGAGAGGAUCAAAGGGUACAGACAAAUCAAGGAACGUGAGAGAAGUGGUAUGGCUGAGAUGGAUUGAAUAAAGGAGCAAUGAGAGCUCCCUGCAAUGUGUGUGGUACCACUGAGGAUUCUAAAUUAACCUUCAUUAAGGACUUAGUAGUGACAGAGGUGAAGUGGGGAUAGGUACAUGAUUAAUUUACAUCCAUAUUACAAUGAAACCUUAACAUUUAAGAGGGAUAUUAUUGAUGUCUUCAUGAUCCAGAAGAAUCCUCACCUUUGCAACCAUCACUAUAGUCACUUCUUGAGAAUUAUGGCCUUUAAGACUGUAGCAUGCAAUGACAAAACCUCACAGAGGUAUGGGUUCUGCCCGCACACUAAUUUCACUCAUUAAACAAGUGACUGGCUCCUAUAUCCCAGGCUCUCAGCACGCCUUUGCAAAAUAACAGAUUAUUGCAGCUCUUGGACCUUUGAUGCCUCUGGGAAUAGUCAAAGCCACAGAUGUCAAAUAUGUAAAUGCCAAGAUCUAUUAUAAUUAAAUAGUGCAGGCCUCCUUCAAAGAAAAAAAGCAUGUUGGCUGUGCUGCACGUUCUCCAACCAAAUCAGAAUGUUAAAGCUCGAAGGUAUCUGACCUCCCAUUUUUUAAAUUAUGAAGAUGAAAUUCAGAAAGGGAAGGUAACUUAUCCAAGAUUACAUGGCUAGCUAUGAUAGAAAGUUAGAGUUGGAAAGGACGUUAGAAAGUGAGGGUUUGAAAGGACUUUAGAAGCUGCUUAUUCAAUGUUCUCUCUGCCCUUUCCCAUCUUAGGCUUCUCCAUUUUACUUUUAUCCAUCAAUAAAAUGUUAACUUCAAAAA